ACGCGCAGUGCUCUUGGCCGGGAGGAGGCUGUGCUGCACCAGCACCUCUUGCUCCACAUCUCCAGAGAGCCCAGAUGAUGCUAUUGUUGGAACCUGGGAAGGUCGGAAGGAAUAGCUGAGUGAAGAAAACACCAAGGUGACCCUCUUUAUAGAUCAGAAAACAGGCCUGGAGGGGACCCACGCCUUGCCCAAGGUCACAGGUUGGAUACAGCAGAGCUGGCCUCCAACCGUGGAGCCCGUGCACUUAACAUCUAUUUGGAUGGAAGGCUCGAAGGUUACCUGAGACAACCUGGUCAAGGUGAUAAUGUGGGAGAAUGUGGCCAGUGGUUCCCAGAUGAGUGAAUGAUCAGUGUGCAGUCACCAGAGGAUGGGUGAUAAACCGAGAACCACAAGCUCUUAACACUGUGGGGUGGGCGAGGCUUCAUCUCCCAGGAUGCAGCACUUGCUGAGUUGGGCAACAGGGGACCCUGGUUGAUGGCCCAGGUUGGUUGGAAGCCUUUGGGAGAUGUGCUCUGUGUUGGUGGGGAAGGCCAGGCAUGGUUAGAUCCCCUGUAGACUUGGGGAGCUCAGUUUCAGAAAGUUUCAAAGAUCAUCACUUGAUUUCUGUGAUUCACGUGAUCUGAGGGCUCUGAAAGUGGUGGGUGAGUCCUGGAAUUAAAUCUGUUUUUUUCAAGUAGGAAAGACAUGGGGUGGCAAUGAGAGACAUCUGUGUGGCUCAGAAAGAUGUCUUGCUGAGGUCAGAGGGACAAGAGCCAAGGAGAACAAGAGGAGCCCUUCCCAGGACACUCACAAUGACAGAGUGACGAGGGCCAGUAAAGAGUGUCAGGGGGUGAGAGCCCGGGUGUGAACUGAACCUACUGAGGAGAGCUGACGACCACAAAGCAUCUUUUCAUAUCAUGUUCGGAGCAAGGAGAACAAGGGCUUCAUAGAUCCAUCGCCGUCUAGGGCAGCUGGUGUCUGUGAAGGGGAGGAAGGCACAGCUCCACUGUGCCCACAGCGGUCUGGACAGAGGAGGAUCUGCAGGUGCAAAGGGCGCAGGCAGGUUCCCGGAGGAAAGCAGGAGCCACGUAGCGUGGGCUGCAGUGUGUGUGCUCAGGGCUCUGACCAAGAGAAUGCCCUGGCCAGGGUAUAGCAUGACCUGGAAUGAGAUACCCCCAUCUGAGGUGCUGUCUGAGAGGUGUUGGAAAUGAAGCCCGGAGGUGGAAGAGACUCAAAUCUGAUGUUGGCCCUGGGAAAGAUCCUAGACUAAGAAGAAGGCUGUGAGUCUGUGGGCAAAGGAGAGACGUGCAUGAGGAGCUGGCGGGGGCUCCCUGGGGACAAGUCAUGCCAGCCUCACGUCAUUUUCCACCUUGCAGGUCUUCGGUCUGGCCCUUGUUCUGUUGGGGUUCUGGAGGACGUGCUGUGCCCUGGCCUUACUGACCUUACUCCAUGCAGUGCUGAUGCAUGCGACAGCGGUGACCCUCCAGGGUCCCAGGGCCCUGUGGCCGAGUGUGUCCAGCCCAGUGUCAUGGGGAGCUUCCAUAUCUCAUGGCUCCUUGCUGGGCCAAGCCCUCCAGAACCCCAAACCCCCAAAGACUGAUGAAUGCCAGAGUGGCCACCUUGCUUAUCUGUGGCCCCGGCCCUGGUGAUCACCAUGGCAGCUGGGAAGGGAGCCCCGUUGAGCCCAUCGGCUGAAAACAGAUGGCGACUUAGCGAACCUGAGCUGGGCCGGGGCUGCAAGCCAGUGCUGCUCGAGAAGACGAACCGCCUGGGCCCUGAGGCUGCUGUGGGCAGGGCGGGCCGGGAUGUGGGCAGUGCGGAGCUGGCACUGUUGGUAGCCCCAGGCAAGCCCCGACCUGGCAAGCCGCUGCCCCCGAAGACACGUGGAGAGCAGAGGCAGAGCGCCUUCACGGAGCUGCCGAGGAUGAAGGACCGGCAGGUGGAUGCUCAGGCCCAGGAGAGGGAGCACGAUGACCCCACAGGCCAACCUGGUGCCCCACAGCUGACCCAGAACAUCCCCAGAGGCCCAGCUGGCAGCAAAGUCUUCUCUGUGUGGCCCAGCGGAGCACGAAGUGAGCAAAGAAGCGCCUUUAGCAAACCAACCAAGCGACCAGCAGAGAGGCCUGAGCUAACCUCAGUCUUCCCUGCAGGGGAAUCUGCAGAUGCCCUGGGGGAGCUGUCUGGACUCCUCAACACUACAGACCUCGCUUGUUGGGGUCGACUUUCAACUCCCAAGCUUUUGGUUGGUGAUUUGUGGAACUUGCAAGCAUUGCCACAGAAUGCUCCACUCUGUAGCACUUUUCUGGGUGCCCCUACACUGUGGCUGGAGCAUACCCAGGCCCAGGUGCCCCCACCCUCAUCAUCCUCCACCACUUCGUGGGCCCUCCUGCCACCCACCCUCACCUCCCUGGGCUUGUCCACCCAGAACUGGUGUGCAAAGUGCAACCUGUCCUUUCGCCUAACGUCCGACCUGGUCUUUCACAUGCGAUCCCACCACAAAAAGGAGCAUGCGGGGCCUGACCCACAUUCUCAGAAGCGGAGAGAAGAGGCCCUUGCCUGCCCUGUGUGCCAGGAGCACUUCCGGGAGCGCCACCACCUCUCCCGGCACAUGACUUCUCACAGCUAGCAGGUGACCGCAGAAUGACCUGCUGGGUGCAGCAGCCAGCCUUUGGCAGAGGGGGGCUCCCUGGGCCUGCGUUGAGGGGGCUGUCAUGGUCCUUUGCAGAGCUGCUGCUUUUGGCAUUCAUAGAUAAACAGCUCAGGCAUAAUUUGAAAAAGCCACACCUGCAUGAUGUGUUUUGAAGGAAAUGAAGUCCUGAAAUAAAGUGAUGGGCUUUGCAAAUCCAGGGUAGAGGCCCUAACAGGCACAGAGAGCAGGGGCAACUCCUGGCACACAUCAUGGGCUUUGGAGGCACACAAGCCUGGAUUCGAAUCUGGGCUCUUUCACAUACUAGCUGUGACCCUGGACAAAGAGCUUUAACCUGCUGAGUCCCCAUUUUCUCAUCUGUGAAAUGGAGAUGAUAACACUGUGUCUUAGGUUGGCAUUCAGGUCACAUGAAAGGUGUGUGGAAAGUGGCCAGCAUUCUGCCUGCAGACCCUGAGCACUGAGUCAACAAGGUUUGUGAUGAUGUCUGUACUAGUUAGCUAUUGUUAUUAACAAGAUCUCCAUGGCAGACAAGCUAAAGCAUCUGCCUAAGUCGUGAGUCUGUGGGUUGGCUCAGGUUAAGCUGAGCUUGGCUGGGCUUGGCAGCAAGUCUCAGAUUUGAUCAAGUCAUAUUCGUUUUCUUCUUCGGCUGGUGGGCUACCCAGAGCGAGCACGCUUCUCUCGUGGUCAUGCCAAGAACACAGGAGGGUGAGUCUAACAAGCACACCUCAAGCCUCUGCUUGGGUCACAUUGCCAAUGUCCUCUCAGCCCAUACAAGUGGCAGGACCAGGCCCAAUAUUAAGGAGUGGAAAAGUGUAGGCUGCCCUUGGUGAAGCUGUGACAAGGGAGUGACCAUCCAUCCCCUCCACAGGAGGGUGAGGAAUUGGGACAGGUAAUUCCAGCCAAUACCUGGUCCAUAGUUCUUCACAUUGUGAGUAUAUGAAUACGGGGAAAUAGAACCCCCUCCCCACCACCUACACACAUGCUGUUUUACCUUCCAAGAAUAGGACAUGUGCAAAAACUAGGCUUCCAGAUCGUGAGGCUGGGGAGCAUUCUAGGUACCAUUUAUUAUCUACUGCGUUUCGGUCAGUAGCUGUUGUAGGUACCCGCAUCAGCCCUUGUUCCUAAGGAUGUGUGGAGCCCAGGCUGUACUCUUUGACAUUCCACAGGUCAGUCUGCGUGAAAGCCCUUUGUGGGGAGUUUCCAAGCCAGUGUCGUUUUUGCACUGGUUUCCACCUCACUGUCAGAUAUUGUUCUUUUGAUAUGCAGUUUCCAGCCCUCCAAUGAGUCCCCAGCACAGAUCUCAGGCUUGUGGCUGGGAAUAAGCCCAGCUGAGCAGGUGGGGAUCUCAGCCAGCCUCCCAGACUGCACCUCUUCUAUUGCUCUCCUCUGUCCACCGUUCCAGGCAGCAGCACUCCCACCUGGCUGCUCUGAUGUCCUCGCUCCCUCCAUUCCUGCCUCUCACCAUGCACGCAUCCAUUGUCCACACACACACAACCAGAUAAUCUUCUGAAAGUGUAACUCAGAUGAUGCCUCCAACCCUGUGGCUGCCCUUCACACUUACAGGCCUAACCCCAGCAGGACCUGCCAGCUGCUUCAUGAACAAGUCCCUGCCUCAUGUUAAUUGCAAGCACUCAUUUCACUCUCCCUGUGUGCCAGGCAAUAGCAUAAGCACUGGAAGAAUACAGAUGUUAUAGUGAGUCCUACAAUAGCCCUGGAAGGCAAGAGCUGUUUCCUUUCCAUUUCUACAAUGAGUCAAUUGCAGAUGAUGCUAUAACACUUCCAGUGUUUCUGACACUUCCCUGAAGCUAUACCUGCUACCUUCAUGGGCCGAGCUUGCCCUUAUGAGGCCCACAGGUGGCAGUGGGCAGAGGGGACCCCGCUAUACCACCUCGCUGCUGUUCCACUGUCUGCUCCCGUGUUCUGACCACAGCUCUGGUGCCGUUUCUCAAGCCUGGGCUUCAUUCAACAUUUUCUAUCUAGCUCUUCAUGGUGCUGCUCCUGCUAUGGUUCCACAGGGCUUCUUCUCGCAGGUCAGCUCCUUAGAGAGGUCUCCCAGAUUCCCCGUAAAGCAGCCCUGCAGCCUCUGCCUCUCUCAGCCGCAUCACCCUGUUGCUUCCUUCACAGCAUGUCUCACCAUCUGCAACCAUCUUUCUGUUUGUCGUCUUGUUGAUUUGCUGCCUCCACACUGUCAGCUCCUUGGGAACAGAGAUUGGUUUGUUUACUGUGCAUCCCUGGUGCCCAGAACAGGGCAUGGCAUAUUGUUGGUGCAUAAUAAAUAUUGUGGAAAUAA